GUAGGAAGGCGCCGGCCGUGGAGGCGCCACGUCCCUUGCGGCGGCGGGAGAGAAAUCGCUUGGACUUCGGGGCGGCCUCGGACGGCCAUGGCCUUUACCCUGUACUCACUGCUGCAGGCAGCCCUGCUCUGCGUCAACGCCAUCGCAGUGCUGCACGAGGAGCGAUUCCUCAAGAACAUUGGCUGGGGAACAGACCAGGGAAUUGGUGGAUUUGGAGAAGAGCCGGGAAUUAAAUCACAGCUAAUGAACCUUAUUCGAUCUGUAAGAACCGUGAUGAGAGUGCCAUUGAUAAUAGUAAACUCAAUUGCAAUUGUGUUACUUUUAUUAUUUGGAUGAAUAUCAGUGGAGAAAAUGGAGACUCAGAAGAGGACAUGCCAGUAGAAGUUAUUACUUUGGUCAUUAUUGGAAUAUUUAUAUCUUAGCUGGCUGACCUUGCACUUGUCAAAAAUGUAAAGCUGAAAAUAAAACCAGGGUUUCUAUUUAUCUGUUUUUUUUUUUAAUGUUGCACUUGUAGUUUCAUUACAAAAGAUCAGAUCAUGAAAGGCAGUAACUCUCCAGGACUGGAAUAUCUGAUUGCUCAGUGUUAAUAGUAGUUCAUGCUGUGGUGAGAUUGUUAAAAGGGUGCAAGACUGUUGCUUCUCUUUUUUUAGAUAUUUUUCUAUCUCUCACUUCUCAGGGAUGAAAUUCUUUUUCAAAGUUUUGAAGUUCCUUGCAACUUAGCCAUGAUGUGAGUGGUUAUCCCUAGAUAAAAUUAAAAGGAUUUUUAAAAAGUAAUUACUGCACAUAAAAUGAUAAAUAGGUAAUUUGAAUAAUUUUAUUUUAAGCUCCUUGGUUAAUUAUUUUGUCUAUUGUCUCAGCUAUAAAUUCAAAUUUAUACAUACUAUUGAGUAUUAAUAUUCUCUGAUUUCAGGGAGAAUUCUGUCAGUCACAUGAUGAUUAUGUUUUUGUUUAACAUUCUUUCCAUGCACUUGUUAUUUUAUUAAUUUGCCUGAAUGAUGAGACCAGACCAGUGUCUACAGAUUUUCAUUGUCAGAAAAAUCUAUAAGUCUGCCCUUUUUACAAUGAUGAUUUAAAAAAAACAACAGCGUAAAUAUUAGCCCACAAGAGCAGUCCUAAACAAUCACAAUUACACUGUACUACCCAAGAAGACUGUUUAUUGUGAAGCAUUUACCUUUCAAAAAAUCAUUACAUUUCUAUUUCUUGGUGGAGCAGCACAUUGUGGAGUGUGAUUCUUAAUUCUUCAUUGAGUUUGUCAAUAGGACAUUGAUGCUGGAUAGGUUGUCUUUUGUUUUUAUGUCUCAGACCAUCUUGUGAGAUUGUUUGCCUAUCUCAUAAUACAGUUUUAUGCAGAAAGGUUGAAACUAUGUAAAUGGUUUUUAUGGAAAUUAUCAGUUACAAUAUUUUAAAGGUGUAGAAUGGCAUCUUUGUUUAUAGGAGAACAUUUGUAAAUAAAGUUAAAUUUCUAAGUCAAGCACUUGUUUUUGUACCUUAGUAUAAACCUGUCAGUGUUAACUGCAUUAAUCUCCAUUUUGGGUGAACACCUCUUAUUAUAUGUUCUUUGCUGUAAAAUUGCCGAGUAUAGAGUUAAUGAAAGUAAAUAUUUACAUGUAUUUUUUUUUCUUCAGUGAAUUAACUGAAUUGCUGACAUACAUCCAGAAGACUCAUGAGCACCUUUUAUUUCAUGACUUCAGUUACUUCUAAAACUAUGGAGCAGGUAUUAAGUACCUUUUGGCCUUUCCUAAGUUAGAGAUCAGUGAUCUUUGGACUAUAGGCUUGCAGCUAGUCCAAGGAAAGUACCAAGGAUUCUUAGUUGAUUACUUGGCUCAUGUGAAUGACUAAUUUGGUACUUAGAGGCCGUGUUCUUUUAGCCUUACAAAGAACUGAUGCCUGAGUUCAAGUUUGAGCUACUGAAAAGAUUCAAAAGAAGCAGUUACUUGAGGGCAGGCCCAUUUCCCCAUAUGGUAUGAGCAGUACAAAAUUUUUUAAAAUGAAAGAAAAGAGAGACCUUGAUCUGAUGUUAUUUUUCAUAUAAGACAUUACAGCAUACCUUCAUCUUAAUUCAGUGUUGGGAUUUUGUCCAAAUAUUCCAUCAGGGAGCAGUCACAGAAGGGCCAGGAUCAAAGUAUUCUGUAGCCAAGUAGUUCUGAGGAAAGUGAAGCACUGAACUGAACAUCAAAAUAUGUCAUAUCUGGAGGCCACUUCAUAAUUCCAGUUUGUGGCUGAAGAGGGGUCUGUAAGCUUUCACUGGUCAGCCCUGGUUUCCCCAGAGCAGUUGUGAUUCAGUAAACAGAGUGUGUUAUUUUAGUAGACAGUAACUUAAGUGCCUGUUGGCCUGCCCAUGUCCUCCCCUUUAUCUAUUACCAGGAUUAACAAUUUGUGAUGAUUCUGGACUCCAAAUACCGAUGAUGUUUAUAGUCCUUAUGUAUUCUGGCCCUGUGUUUGCAUGUCUCUGAACUGUGCGAAGGUUCUUGGCUCUAGUCUGUAGAUAUUAACCAAAUUCAUCGCUAAUCAAGUACAGUGGUUUUCAAACUUUUAUAGUUAACAGCAGAACCAGAUUUUCAAAGGAAUUCUGACACAGAACUGUAACAUUCCCGUAUCUAAACCAGAUGAGAGUAGGUCCAUUUAUUUGUUUUUAGUUGAAGUAGAGCUGGGAUUCAAAGGCUCACUAUUCAGCCUCCACUGCACUCUUGUCAGGCUUCCCAAGGCAUUUCCAUAAAACCCUAAAUUUUCAAAAAUAUAGCUAAAAAGUAUCUUAUAAAAAUCCCUGCUUUAGCCAUAAAAAAGAAUUAGAUAAUACCUUCUGUGGGAACAUGGAUGGAGCUGGAAGCCAUCAUCCUUAACAAACUAAUGUAGGAACAGAAAACCAAAUACCACAUGUUAUUACUUAUAAGUGGGAGCUAAAUGAUAAGACCUCAUGGACAUAAGGAGGGGGACAACAGACACUGGGGGCUAUUUGAGGGUGGAGGGUGAGAAAGAGUGCCAGAAAAAUUACUGGGUACUAGGCUUAGCACCUGGAUAACGAAAUAAUCUGUGCCAAACCCCCGUGACACAAGUUUACCUAUUUAACAAAUGUACUGUACCCCUAAAAGUUAAAAAAGUAAAAAUAUAAAAAAAUAAAAUCCCUGCUUUAGGGAGGGUGGGAGGGGGUGAGGGAAACAGAAACUACAUACUGAGUACAAUGUACAGUAGUCCAGUGAUGGGUGCACUAAAAUUUCAGACUUUACACCACUAUACAAUUCAUCCAUGUAACCAGAAACCACUUGUACCCCUAAAGCUAUUGAAAUAAAAAGCUAAAUGAGUUCCCCCACCUUCCUCUCCCCAUCAAAAUCCUUGCUUUAGAUACAAUAAGAGUAGGCAAUCUGUGUUCUAUAUGUGUUAGAUGUGUAUUACUGGUGAAAUGACAAGAGAAAGCAAGAUAUUUGACUAGUAAAAAGACUAGGAGGCAAGAUAUUUCUAAUAUAUCAAGCAAACCUUUUACCAUGUGACUGAAAGCAAAUAAACUUCCUAAGACCUCAGUAGUUUUUGGUUGUCCUAUCUGUAAAAUUGGUCAAUAACCUUCAGAACAGAAGUCUGGUCCAGAUAUAUAUAUAUAUCUUUUCCAGAUCACUAAUGUUUGUAUCUAGAUGUGCUUCAACCAAAGAGAUGUUCUCCUUAAGUAAAAUGUUUCUUAUGAAGCAAA